AAUUCGCGCUCGGGAGUGAGGAGCCGCCAACACCCCAGCUCCGCUGCUGCCGCCACCGCAGUGCUCUCUAGUCGCCAUUGGUUACCUAAACUUUCCAGUACCCGCGACCUUUCCGGGACUCCGCGGCGGCGGGGCAGAGGCGGCCCAGGGGCGGCACGCGGCUGCUCCGGUGCGCCGGGCUCUUUUCGGCCGCCGCACGGCCGGGCCUCACAGGCUGCCCUCCUGAGAGAGGCUCAGAACACGGCCAGGUACGCGCCGCCGCCACAGUUGCGCUGCUAGCGACGAGGUGUUUUCCUCUGCUGGCACGCCAGAAUCCCUGGUUCAGCCUGGAAGGCGAGGGGCAGGACUCCCCAGACAGUGGCCUCAGUGUGGCAUUGAUGUCCUAGGUUGUAAGGUGCUAAGGGGAAUGCCAGCUGUUCUCUUAACAGAAGGGCAGUUUUUGAAGAAAUGAAGCAGGACUUGAUGUGGAUUGUCAUAAACUGUUUCUCCCUAAAGAGGCUGGUCCCCACAGACGGCUUGCCAUUUCUAUGACUGGAUGCUGAGAAGCCUGCUGGUUCAGAGGUCCACACAUGAAGUUACCAUAAAGAGGGUGGUUCCAACUUCAUCAAUACCUCAUCGCCAUGAGGUGAGGCUAAGAUGAGCAUAACCAGUGACGAGGUGAACUUUCUGGUUUAUCGGUAUCUCCAGGAGUCAGGUUUUUCUCACUCGGCUUUCACGUUUGGGAUCGAGAGCCACAUCAGCCAGUCCAACAUCAAUGGGACACUAGUGCCACCGUCUGCCCUCAUCUCCAUUCUCCAGAAGGGACUGCAGUAUGUAGAGGCUGAGAUAAGCAUCAACAAGGAUGGCACAGUGUUCGACAGCCGCCCUAUAGAGUCCCUGUCCCUGAUAGUUGCUGUGAUUCCUGAUGUGGUGCAGAUGCGGCAGCAGGCAUUUGGAGAGAAGCUCACUCAGCAGCAAGCCAGUGCAGCAGCCACAGAGGCAUCAGCAAUGGCAAAGGCGGCAACCAUGACCCCAGCUGCUAUUUCCCAGCAAAAUCCUCCAAAGAACCGAGAGGCCACAGUGAACGGGGAAGAGAAUGGAGCACAUGAAAUCAAUAAUCACUCAAAGCCAAUGGAAAUAGAUGGGGAUGUUGAGAUUCCACCCAACAAAGCCACAGUCCUUCGGGGCCACGAGUCUGAGGUGUUCAUUUGUGCCUGGAACCCUGUCAGUGAUUUGCUAGCCUCUGGAUCUGGAGACUCAACUGCAAGGAUAUGGAACCUGAAUGAGAAUAGCAACGGGGGCUCCACCCAGCUCGUGUUGAGACAUUGUAUACGAGAAGGGGGGCACGACGUCCCAAGUAAUAAAGAUGUCACCUCACUGGACUGGAACAGUGAUGGAACACUAUUGGCUAUGGGUUCAUAUGAUGGUUUCGCAAGAAUAUGGACAGAAAAUGGUAACCUGGCCAGCACCUUAGGCCAACAUAAAGGCCCCAUCUUCGCUCUGAAAUGGAACAAAAAGGGGAAUUAUGUUUUGAGUGCUGGUGUAGACAAAACAACAAUAAUUUGGGAUGCUCACACAGGAGAAGCCAAACAGCAGUUUCCUUUUCAUUCAGCCCCCGCCCUUGAUGUGGACUGGCAGAACAACAUGACCUUUGCCUCCUGUAGCACAGACAUGUGUAUCCAUGUGUGCAGGCUCGGCUGUGACCACCCAGUCAAAACCUUCCAGGGACACACAAACGAGGUCAAUGCCAUCAAAUGGGAUCCUUCUGGAAUGUUGCUGGCGUCCUGCUCGGAUGACAUGACAUUGAAGAUCUGGAGUAUGAAGCAGGAUGCAUGCGUCCACGAUCUUCAGGCUCACAGCAAAGAGAUCUACACCAUCAAGUGGAGCCCCACCGGGCCUGCCACCAGCAACCCAAACUCCAGCAUCAUGUUGGCAAGUGCUUCAUUUGAUUCUACAGUGCGACUGUGGGAUGUGGAGCAAGGUGUCUGCACCCACACACUCAUGAAGCAUCAAGAGCCUGUCUACAGUGUAGCUUUCAGCCCCGAUGGAAAGUACUUGGCUAGUGGAUCCUUUGACAAGUAUGUUCAUAUCUGGAAUACUCAGAGUGGAAGUCUCGUCCACAGCUACCAAGGCACUGGCGGUAUCUUCGAGGUGUGCUGGAACGCCCGAGGAGAUAAAGUGGGCGCCAGCGCGUCUGAUGGCUCUGUGUGUGUUCUGGAUCUGUGAAAGUAAACACAAAAUAUAGAAAAAAAGAAAAGAAUUCUAAUGACCUGCCUUGAAUGCAUGGGGUUGCAGCUCUGUUCAAACACAAUUCUAUCAGCUCCAAAAUGUGUGAACUUGACUUGUGUUAGAGUAUAUUCUGAAACCAACUUGUCCCAGGCCACAGGAGUGUAUAUGUUUCAUAAUCUUUAUCAAGA